AUCCUGCAGCUCCAAAACCCAGUCUCUUGUUGCAUUUUACUCUAAGCAGUCAGGAGAAACCAAGCCAAUUCUCAAGAGACGAUAACCAAUAGAACCCAAGUAUUUGGGAUUUGGUGUGGAAGAGGCAGAAAAGAGCAGGUCCUGAGGGAAAGAUAAUGUUUGAGAAGCAAAGCAAGAAAAGAUGAUGACAAACACAACACUCAAAGGCCCUAGACAUCAUCACUUUUUUUACCAUCAUGAACAUUUAAACAUAACACAUUUUCUUUUUUUUCUAAUUUCAUCUCCCUCUUCCUUCCCUGGUCUCCAAAGCGGCAGGCUUGAGUGGACUGCUCCCGGGAAGCCACUUUCAUGGCGUCCCCUCUCCAGGGUGCCCAUCUACCUGGAGCGUCAUCAUCGUCACUGCUGGAGUCUUGUCUCCUGUUGCCAAUCCAAGCUCUGGAGACACAAGUACCACAAGAAAGGUGUUACCCAGAGGCACUCGCCCAUCCUCCCUGCUGCACCGGAGGCCACACCAGCUGCCACAGCAACUCCCUGCUCCGUCCUCUGCUUUCUCAGAACUAACCUGGGCUCUCUGGAAUCAGAGACCUUCAACAAGUCACUGCUCACAUUUGCAAAUGUUCACGUCAAGAGAGGACCCCCUUUCCACGUGCCACUCCCCUCUCUUCCGGAUCAUUGCAGCUCUCCCCACCAGCCUUAUCAAUGUGGGGCUCCAACCCUACAGGUCAGUGAUUCACAAACAGGCACUGUCCCAGGUUGGAGCCACUGCCACGAGCCUGUUCUGCACAGACGGGAAUGUUUCCUCUGCCUUGUGAGCGCAGGGCUAUCGGGCACUGGAAAUAUGCCUGAUGUGAUGAGGUACUGGAGAUUACAUUUGAAAAUUAAUUUAAAAUACAGAUGCACCUGGUUAAUGACUGUGGCACCAGGGAGUCCAGAACUGGGAUUCAGAGAUGAGGGAGACGUCACCUCCCCGCCUCUGGGUUUUCCUUCCAGUGUAGCCAUCAAUGGCCUAGUGUUAUCUUUCAUCCAGUACGUACUUCCUGGGCACAGGCAUAAGUAUCCAGUGCUCUGUGAGACCCUAGGGGUGCUGAACACUGAGUCACAUCCAGGUCCUAGAGGGGUUCACAUCUGGGGGCGAUGUGUAAACAGAGUGAAGGGCAUGGCCAGCAAAUCCUGUGCUGGAAAAUCAGGGCAGCUGGAGUGAGGGGAGGGGACACCCCACUGUCCCCAGGAGCCCACACACCAGCCGAAUUUGGCUUUUAAUUCACCUUUCUUGUGAUGUCUUUUGCUGAAUUUGCUGUCAUGAUUGUCCCGAUUAAAAGAGAGCAUUGUGUGUUCCCUCUAUAUCCAGAAGUGUGCAUGCAAGAUUGGAGUUACUUCUAUUUAAAAUAUGUGAUGGACUCAGAGGGGACAGUAAGGAUGGAAGUUUGCGUAUGGAAAAAUAGUUUGCGUUACUUUGUUUUUAUUUGAUGGUUGCUUUACUUGUGGUGCAGUGCACAGUAUAUUACCUGUACAGAUUGUUGCCUUCUGACAAACACUGUGUUACCACCGCCCAGAUAUGAACACCCUGGCAGCCGCUCUUUGGCUAAUUCCUAGGCAGUAACUUCCAAGAGACACUCACUAUUCUGGUCAUGAUCAACAUAUUUUAAAUUUAUUUUUAAACACUGUAUAAAUGGAAACCUACAGUAUGUACUCUUUUGUGCCUGAAUGAAAAUUACACGUGAAUAUCAUGUAAAUUUCACCUAUGUUCCAUUGUGAUGACACAUUCAGCAUUUUGUACUGCUCGGUCCUGUCCAUAUAUAACAUCUACAUUGUAGGAAGUUGGCACAAUGAGUUUUCACCCUCUAUGUUUUACAUUCACUCUGUUUAUCAUGAUGGUUAUAAGGGAGGAGACCUCCCCUUAUAUUGUCUUAUGCCCAAUUUCUGCCUCCAAAGAAAGAAGAAGUAAAAACUAAAAGGCAGAAAUGAAAUCCACAAGCAGACAGCCCAGCACCACACCCUGGGCCUGGUAGUUAAAGGUUGACCCCUGACCUAAUCGGUUAUGUUAUCUAUAGAUUACAGAGAUUGUAUAGAAAAGCACUGUGAAAAUCCCUGUCCUGUUCUGUUCCAUUCUAAUUACCGGUGCAUGCAGCCCCCAGUCACGUACCCCCUGCUUGCUCAAUCGAUCAUGACCUUCUUACGCAGACACUUUUAGAGUUGUGAGCCCUUAAAAGGGACAGGAAUUGCUCACUCGGGGAGCUCAGUUGUUGGAGACGUGAGUCUUGCCGAAGCUCCCAGCUGAAUAAAGCCGUUCCUGCUUUAA